AGUCCAUAUAGAGCUGUCCUACAGCAUUCUGGAAACUUGAGGAUGUGCGGUGCAUAAAGGGGCUGGAAGUGACCCACCUGUGAUGAGCCCUUUCUAAGGAGAAGGGUUUCCAAGAGAUCACCCCACCAGAAAAGGGUAGGAAUGAGCAAGUUGGGAAUUUUAGACUGUCACUGCACAUGGACCUCUGGGAAGACGUCUGGCGAGAGCUAGGCCCACUGGCCCUACAGACGGAUCUUGCUGGCUCACCUGUCCCUGUGGAGGUUCCCCUGGGAAGGCAAGAUGCCCAACAACAGCACUGCUCUGUCAUUGGCCAAUGUUACCUACAUCACCAUGGAAAUUUUCAUUGGACUCUGCGCCAUAGUGGGCAACGUGCUGGUCAUCUGCGUGGUCAAGCUGAACCCCAGCCUGCAGACCACCACCUUCUAUUUCAUUGUCUCUCUAGCCCUGGCUGACAUUGCUGUUGGGGUGCUGGUCAUGCCUUUGGCCAUUGUUGUCAGCCUGGGCAUCACAAUCCACUUCUACAGCUGCCUUUUUAUGACUUGCCUACUGCUUAUCUUUACCCACGCCUCCAUCAUGUCCUUGCUGGCCAUCGCUGUGGACCGAUACUUGCGGGUCAAGCUUACCGUCAGAUUCAGAAUUCCUGGGCUCCCUGGGUGCAUUCUAUCAUUCCAGUUGAAAGUUUGCUUCCUUCCAGUCAUGUGGCUCUUCAUUCUACUCUCCUUGGCUCUCAUUUCAGAUGCCAUGGUCAUGGAUGAAAAGGUCAAGAGAAGCUUUGUGCUGGACACGGCUUCUGCCAUCUGCAACUACAAUGCCCACUACAAGAAUCACCCCAAAUACUGGUGCCGAGGCUAUUUCCGUGACUACUGCAACAUCAUCGCCUUCUCCCCUAACAGCACCAAUCAUGUGGCCCUGAGGGACACAGGGAACCAGCUCAUUGUCACUAUGUCCUGCCUGACCAAAGAGGACACGGGCUGGUACUGGUGUGGCAUCCAGCGGGACUUUGCCAGGGAUGACAUGGAUUUUACAGAGCUGAUUGUAACUGACGACAAAGGAACCCUGGCCAAUGACUUUUGGUCUGGGAAAGACCUAUCAGGCAACAAAACCAGAAGCUGCAAGGCUCCCAAAGUUGUCCGCAAGGCUGACCGCUCCAGGACGUCCAUUCUCAUCAUUUGCAUACUGAUCACGGGUUUGGGAAUCAUCUCUGUAAUCAGUCAUUUGACCAAAAGGAGGAGAAGUCAAAGGAAUAGAAGGGUAGGCAACACUUUGAAGCCCUUCUCGCGUGUCCUGACUCCAAAGGAAAUGGCUCCUACUGAACAGAUGUGACUGAAGAUUUUUUUAAUUUAGUUCAUAAAGUGAUGCUACAACAGAAUAAUCACCAUGACAACUGGCCCACACCUCAGAGACUGAUUCUGAUCUCCCAGGAAUUCUGAAGGACCCUCUAUCCUUGACAACAAUCAUUUGCAGCCAGGUAGCAACGGCGGUAGUCAGAGGAGCUAUGAUAGACCACACCCAAGCAAGGCUGCCCUCAAAUAACAUCUCAAGAUCUUAGUUCUUAUGCAUUCCAUCAGUCAGAAGUGAAGAAGAGGUGGAGAAUCUGGAUUGGGGACCAGGAAAUCACUUGUAUUUUGUUAGCCAAUAAAUUCCUAGCCAGUGUUGAAUGAA